ACCACACCAGCCGGGGAGCCGCCGCCGCCGCCGCCACCUCUGAGCAGCCGGCUGGGAGCGAGAGCCGACAGCUAGUCUGCAAGCCACCGCUGUCGCCAUGGGGAGCCGCGUCUCGCGGGAAGACUUCGAGUGGGUCUACACCGACCAGCCGCACGCCGACCGGCGCCGGGAGAUCCUGGCAAAGUAUCCAGAGAUAAAGUCCUUGAUGAAACCUGAUCCCAAUUUGAUAUGGAUUAUAAUUAUGAUGGUUCUCACCCAGUUGGGUGCAUUUUACAUAGUAAAAGACUUGGACUGGAAAUGGGUCAUAUUUGGGGCCUAUGCGUUUGGCAGUUGCAUUAACCACUCAAUGACUCUGGCUAUUCAUGAGAUUGCCCACAAUGCUGCCUUUGGCAACUGCAAAGCAAUGUGGAAUCGCUGGUUUGGAAUGUUUGCUAAUCUUCCUAUUGGGAUUCCAUAUUCAAUUUCCUUUAAGAGGUAUCACAUGGAUCAUCAUCGGUACCUUGGAGCUGAUGGCGUCGAUGUAGAUAUUCCUACCGAUUUUGAGGGCUGGUUCUUCUGUACCGCUUUCAGAAAGUUUAUAUGGGUUAUUCUUCAGCCUCUCUUUUAUGCCUUUCGACCUCUGUUCAUCAACCCCAAACCAAUUACGUAUCUGGAAGUUAUCAAUACCGUGGCACAGGUCACUUUUGACAUUUUAAUUUAUUACUUUUUGGGAAUUAAAUCCUUAGUCUACAUGUUGGCAGCAUCUUUACUUGGCCUGGGUUUGCACCCAAUUUCUGGACAUUUUAUAGCUGAGCAUUACAUGUUCUUAAAGGGUCAUGAAACUUACUCAUAUUAUGGGCCUCUGAAUUUACUUACCUUCAAUGUGGGUUAUCAUAAUGAACAUCAUGAUUUCCCCAACAUUCCUGGAAAAAGUCUUCCACUGAGCUGGAGUUUCCUGGAUGGGUGCAGUGGCUCACACCUGUAAUCCCAGCACUUUGGGAGGCCUAGGUGAGGAAAAUAGCAGCUGAAUACUAUGACAACCUCCCUCACUACAAUUCCUGGAUAAAAGUACUGUAUGAUUUUGUGAUGGAUGAUACAAUAAGUCCCUACUCAAGAAUGAAGAGGCACCAAAAAGGAGAGAUGGUGCUGGAGUAAAUAUCAUUAGUGCCAAAGGGAUUCUUCUCCAAAACUUUAGAUGAUAAAAUGGAAUUUUUGCAUUAUUAAACUUGAGACCAGUGAUGCUCAGAAGCUCCCCUGGCACAAUUUCAGAGUAAGAGCUCGGUGAUACCAAGAAGUGAAUCUGGCUUUUAAACAGUCAGCCUGACUCUGUACUGCUCAGUUUCACUCACAGGAAACUUGUGACUUGUGUAUUAUCGUCAUUGAGGAUGUUUCACUCAUGUCUGUCAUUUUAUAAGCAUAUCAUUUAAAAAGCUUCUAAAAAGCUAUUUCGCCAGGCACGGUGGCUCAUGCCUAUAAUCCCAGCACUUUGGGAGGCCAAGGUGGGUGGAUCACCUGAGGUCAGGAGUUCGAGACCAGCCUGGCCAACACGGUGAAACCCCAUCUCUACUAAAAAUGCAAAAAUUAGCCGGGCGUGGCGGCACAUGCCUGUAAUCCCAGCUACAUGGGAGGCUGAGGUGGGAGAAUUGCUUGAACCCAGGAGGCGGAGGCAGAGGCUGCAGUGACCCAAGAUUGUGCCACUGCACUCCACCCUGGGCAACAGAGCAAGACCCCAUCUCAAAAAUAAAUAAAUAUAUAUAAAAAAUAAAAAGCUAUUUCUAGUUUAUUUCACUAUAAAGUUUUGCUUUAUUAAAAAGCUAAUAAACAGCUAUUAAUCACAGUGUAUUAGUAUUUGUUACAUUUUUGUAUUUCACUAUCUUUAUACUAUAUAAUAUGGUAACUUGGGUACCGGGGGAACUUUAAAAUUUCAUCUCAAAAAUAAUUUUUAAAAAGCCUGAGGUAUGAUAUAGCAUAAAAGAUUGAGAUGAAAAUAUAUUUCCCUGUAAGCUGAAUUACUCAUUUAAAAAUUUUAACUUCUAUAUGGGACCCGAAUUAGACACUGCUGAAUCCUGUACAGCCUUACUCAUAAAUAAAGUACUUACUGAAUUUCCACCAUUCAAA